UGGUCACCAGGAAAGACAGAACAAGUGAUAUGUGAAAGCAUCCAUUUGCCAAUAUAAUGUGGAAAUAUCAAGCUUGGUUUGGCUUGGUCAUGGUAUGCUACUUAUUUUAUUUUUCCCUAUUCAUUGGUUCUCUCCCUUUAUCUUCCUUAAACCCAAGCUCCUUCAGAUAUUUAAGAAUCAAAAGUAGGUUCAGCCAGGAAUAUUUAUGUCCUGGGUUAUCCCAUCAAAAGUUUUUUACUGCUGUCUCCUGAAAUGCCAGACUGCCUUGAAUUGGAUUCUGGAAGCUGGGGAUUUGCGGGAGGCGAUUGAAGAGAAAGAGGGACCUUUCCCAGAAGAACUCCUUCAGUGACACGUUGGGCCUUGGGAUUGCCCUGGUUGCAAGGUUUGAGGACUGCCUUUUGCUGGCAAAUAUUGUCAAGAGUCACGGCAGCUACUCUGCCAGAUAAAAUCCACUGAAUCCUGCAGUUAAACUUUUGGCAAGCUAGGAGCCACAUUGUUUCGUAGUAAACUUUGAAGACGUGUUUAACUGGUAAAAUACAGCACCAUUGGAGGCUGAGUGCAUCUGAAGACUUAGGACAAUGAGGCCAGGCCCUGGCUAGGUUGGAGGCUUCUCAAUGAACAUUUACAGCCCCAAGCACAGUUUCUCAGAUGCAGGGAGAGGCUAACCUUUGUCUAGGAGUCCUCAUACAGAGGAACAACCCGCAGAGGGCAUUGCAUUUAGCAGAAACAGAUGCCCCACAGCUCCUUUCCAAAGCUCCCUGGGCCAUGAUUUGCGGGGAGUGUGUUCAAUUUAUCAGAGCCUGAGACACCAGACCAGUUCCCCAGGGUCUCAAGUAGAAUAAACAAGAAAACCUGCAUUUAGCCUUGCAGAUGAGGAGGUGGAUGACCAACCUCCUAACCCCCUCCUUGUCUUACUAAGAGAAUAUCAGCACUGGGCUCUGAAUGACUGAUAGAAGGUGAUGUAAAUAUAUUUUGGCAGUGGCACCAGAUACCAGUGGCGCAUUUGAAGUUCUCCUUCGGUUAAAGGCGUAACUUCUAUUCCAAAGGAGCAGAAUGAUUGAGGGGAGCUGGCAGGUUUCCUGUUCAAGUGCAGAGGGUAGCUUUUGGAAGUCCUUAGAGAGAUGUGACCAAAAUUCCUUGAGGUGGCUUUUAUGGCCUGAUGAUCUGUACCUCUGAAGAGUUUGUAGAUUUUUGACUAUUCAAGUUCUUCCUACCGGCCUGUUUCACUUAGGGAAUCCUGUGCGCUCUGGAGCAUGUGACCCUUGGCAGGUGGGCGCUCUCGCUUGCCUUCCCAUAGAGAUUGCUCCUCACUAGAAAUGUCUCCCCCUUAUUUUGUGAAAUGUGCACGUGUGCAUUUUGGCGUGAGCCUGGUUUAUUGCAGUUGGUGUUUGCAAUGCGUUUAUUUUAUUUCAAGGUGUCAUGUUGAAAGAACCUGUUUUUAGGCUUUUGAAAGCUCAUAUAAACAGGGCUUAUCACCAAUAAGACCGAGUCACUGUUGGAAGGUCCUUACCAACAGGGGGCUCAACUUCAUGCUGCCCAAAUUUCGAUGAGUCUCUUUUGAAAGUACAUACAUCUCAAGCCUUGAGAUUAGAGAAGUGAGACAAAUGCGGAAAAAUUUUUUUAUAUCCGUGGCUUCUUCCCAAAGAGUAUUGCUUGACUCUCCUUGAAAACACAUAAUUUAUAUGUUUUUACUUUUGCCUCUGAGAGAGCUGUUGAGGAUGAGAUGGUGAGUGAGCUGCUUAUCAUAUUUUAUUUACAUUCCUUGUGGUUAUCUUUGUCACAAUCUCUGUUUGCUGUCUGGGGUUUUUUCCUUUUCUUUUCCUUUCACCGUGAUAUAGAAACAUGCCUGUCCGAUUCCUCAGUGAGAAGCCACUUUGCCACUCCCAGGCUCUGUGGCCACAGAGAUAGCAGUGGAUAUCAUGCUGGAUAGGAAACUUGAGAAUGAGUUCUGCUCUUUAAUGAUGUCUGAGCUCCAUGUGCCUUUCACAAAUCUUUAUAAACCUUCUCAUUCGACCUCAUUAAUUUUUUUCUCAUUUAUCUUUAAUACAAACAUUCUAAUUUAGAUGAGCCAGAGUGAAGAAAAUUCGUCAAGGAAACAUUCCCAGAACUUCCUAAUAGGACUAAGGAGUCAAUUUAUUUUAUCAAUACCUAGAAUCAAAAGAGGGGAUGGAAGAAAAUAACCAGACCCUUUCUUGAUGAUAUAGUUCAUAUUCGAUGAAGCUGGUUUGAGAAGUCUGUGUCCCAGGGGAGUGUGAUAGAUCUUUGCGUAGAACAGUCACCCUCUAAAUAAUGGACUUUUGAGUGUAGCAACUGGCUCCGUUGCUCAGGAAAUGGCAUCUUUGAUCAGGUUUGAUUAUCAUUAUUGUUACCCACACUUCUGUGUCCCCACAAAAUGAUGCUGAUAUUUUCUGAUUUGAGGUUUAGCUGUUUGACCCAAAUCCAGCACAGGCAAAGGGACCUAUUGCCCUGAGCAGAGCUGCGCUGGGUAAUUUCUCAUUCAGUCACACAAACCGAGGCAAGUUCAUCUGCUCCCUUGAAUGUUAAAACUUCUAUUGCAUCCCACUCGAGCCCUCGCUGGGAGCUUCUGCCAUUAAAAAUAUAAUAGGAUCAAAAGGGAUGUGAAGAUUUAAUUUACCACCCCAACUUUUUACAGUGAAUAAAUAUGAAUUCUUCUCUUUUCACCUUCCCGUCUGCACAGCAGACUUUUUUUUUUUCUUGGAGGUAUUGAGGAGUGUUAUACAUUUUUAAAGAAGCAGAUUUGAAACAGACUCCUUUCAGAAAAGUAAAGGAGACUUUUCUGAACAAAUAAAAACCCUACUGGUUUUUAUGAAAUAGAGAUGAGAUUACCUCUGGCCUUGAAAUUUUAAAAUUUGUAUGAGUUUCUGGAUUGACUUGAUGAUUGUACUGGGUGGAUCCCUCAGAAGUAACAAACCCAUCCAUGCAAGACUGUGUCCCAUCCAUAGGAACAAGUAUUUUCUCAGAGCAAAUGUCUUCACUGAGCUACCAGAUGCAUUUUCUGGAGGCCUUGAUAGGAGGAGAAAGAUGAAUCAAGACUGACUUAGAAACGAAGGAGGUCAACACAUCCUUAAAGGUCUUUGGUGUAGUUAUUACUAGGAUAGAGUGGAAUGUGAUAGGCGUAUGAGUUCUAGCAGAUUCUAAUUGUGAAGUUUACAUGUAACCAUCUUCUCAUGAGGCAUUCUAUAAAGGUUCCAAUAUAAUCAUCUAGCUGUCUUCACUGAGAUUACCAUUUCUCCAUGGCAGAUUCAGAAAAAACAGCUUUUUAUUCACAAAGCUGGAUUUGAGUUUUGCAGCCUGGGCAAUUUUUUCUGUUCCAUCCAUUACUUCCUUUUUCAUCCUCGUUGUGGCCAAUGUCUGUGUACUAGCACUUCCACAAGAGGGAGAAACACAGUGAAGAGUAGGGAGGACCCCAGAUCCUGAAAAAGCUUUCUUUUGGUUUCUUCUGAAACUUUUGGUUGAUGAAGUGGUUGAAGUUUCCAGCUAAAUACUAUUUGGGGAUUUUAGGAGCCAAAGUCCUCCUCUGAGGAUUAUCUCACCCUUUCUCUGCCUUGUCCUAUCUGGUAGAUGUUGUCUUGACUUGGAGUGUGGAUCGUUCUAGAUUUUUCUUCUCUAUGAUGAUGCCACUUUCACUUUUCCCCUGAGAAGUGAGACUGGAGAACCCUCUAAAACGUCAACUGGAGACCAUUAGCCCUGGCCCAUCAGGCAGGGUGAAAACCGGCAAAUCUGAUACUUUUCCAGGCUGACCAAAUUGACAAAAGGAGCAAGGAUUAAGAAUGGGAAGAUACUAGUAACCUGCUUUUGUGGUGCAGGCACUGUGUGUGGCACUGUGCCGAGGAGCUUUAUUUUAACUAUCUGGCUCAUUUGCAUCCUGUAACCACUUUUAUCCGCAUUUUAGAGAGAAACUGAAGGCCAGAGAGUCGAAGUGAUUUGGCCAGCGUUGAGCAGCUAGAAAUGAACUGAGCUGGAGUUUGAACCAGACAGUUUGGUUCCAAUCCUUACUUCUUAAGCACUUCACCAUAGUGCAGAAGGAUAAGACAGGCACAGUGCAAUGUACAUGUUGGUGCUGUUGUUAUUAAUAAAUACAGUUAGAGCAAUGACUGUUUUGUGGGCUCAGAGAGGCUGCUGUCCUAUUUCUUGCUGAAGCAGUGGGUUGACCAAAGGCUACUCUGUUUUUGGUGGCUCAAAUCUUUGGUGGCACAUAAGCUGCUGUCUCCUAUUGAAGUUAAAAUUCACAAGUGCCAUUGAAGAGCUUUUCAGCUGAAGCACAUAGCAUUUAUCCAAACUAGAGACCUUGAAAGCCGGUGAUUAGGGUGGAUUGUGUACACAUUCAUUCCAAGUUUAGACAAAAAAAAAAUGGGGAGAAGGAGGGAGGAGGUUGGAGAUUUUCAGAGCGGUUGCUUAGAAAAAAGCAACAGCUAUUAUUACAGAGGCACAGGUUUCUCACUAAACCCAUUCUAGAUUUUGUUGUUGUUUUCAUCAAUUGUAGUUGAGUAAGCACAAAACAUCGGGCCCUAUUGUUCAUAAAGAAAACUAGGAGUUGUCAUUAAUCCGGGGCCUUAGUCUCCCUCAGGAAUAAAAUGCUAUCUUACAUCAUUGAGUCUUUCUCCAAGUUUGUCAGCAAAUCUCUUUCAAGCGAUUUGCAAAAUCCUAGCCUGGGAACAAACUCUGUGCCCCUUGCUUAACCAUGGCCUAAUGGCUGUUUCGUGUUGACUGUACUGAGUUAUCUUGGAGUGUUAGGCAACUUUUGCAUUUUGUUUGAUGUUCCAGAUUAGGUCCCUCCCAUACCAAUACCCCUCCACACUGACCCCAUUCUACCAUGAAAAUUAGCCUUGGAGGAGACUCUGGGAGAAUCAGCCUUACAGCUUCAAGGGUACUGGAGAUCAGGCUGCCUUCUACAAGGAGAGAUUUGCAGACACAGAAGCGGCACAGAGAAGGCCAUUGUGAAGAUCAAGGCAGAAACCGGAGUUAUGGCAUCAUAAGCCAAGGAAUGCCAAGGAUUGCUGGCAACCACCUGAUGUUAGAAGAGUCGAGGACAUGUUCUUCUCCAGAGCUUUUGGAUGGUGUGUGGCCCUGCCAACCUUUACAUUUUGGACUUCCAGCCUCCGAAAUGCACUUUCAGACCAUGCUGAAGUCUAAAUUGAAUGUCUUAACACUGAAAAAGGAACCUCUCCCAGCGGUCAUCUUCCAUGAGCCGGAGGCCAUUGAGCUGUGCACGACCACACCGCUGAUGAAGACAAGGACUCACAGUGGCUGCAAGGUUACCUACCUGGGCAAAGUCUCCACCACUGGCAUGCAGUUUUUGUCAGGCUGCACAGAAAAGCCAGUCAUUGAGCUCUGGAAGAAGCACACGCUAGCCCGAGAGGAUGUCUUUCCGGCCAAUGCCCUCCUGGAAAUCCGGCCAUUCCAAGUUUGGCUCCAUCAUCUCGACCACAAAGGGGAGGCCACAGUGCACAUGGAUACCUUCCAGGUGGCCCGCAUCGCCUACUGCACCGCCGACCACAACGUGAGCCCCAACAUCUUCGCCUGGGUCUACAGGGAGAUCAAUGAUGACCUGUCCUACCAGAUGGACUGCCACGCCGUGGAGUGCGAGAGCAAGCUCGAGGCCAAGAAACUGGCCCACGCCAUGAUGGAGGCCUUCAGGAAGACUUUCCACAGUAUGAAGAGCGACGGGCGGAUCCACAGCAACAGCUCCUCCGAAGAGGUUUCCCAGGAAUUGGAAUCCGAUGAUGGCUGAAUGAACUUGAGACGCUUCAGCAAAGGCAGCAUUGGUCACGGAGUUCAAGGGAAUAGAUGAGUAAGCAACGUUUCAAAUUUGGGAUGAAAAGACUGCCAAACUAUUGGCUGACCAAGGUUUUUAAAUUCAGAAGAGCAAUUCUAAAUCUAAAGAAAUGUAUCAUUAAAGUAAUUACGUUACAUUGAAACCUGCUGCUGCUGUGACUGUGAGGAGGGUGGGAGUGUGGAUGGGGAGGAAGGUUCUAGGCUCUCUUAUUUUUCUCAUUUCCCAAUGCCUCUCUGUGGGAGAGCUCCAUGCCAGUUUUCACCACGCUCAGGCAAAUACUCUGCAGCUGUUAUUGGAUGGGCCAUUCCGAUCUGCCUUAUGAAAUUCCACAAGAAUGUUAGGGGCACCUAUGGGAUCUCUAGUGGGGUGGGCAGGGUGCUGAUGGGGACGCUGGCCGCAGGGAGGAAGGAACAUCUCGGGAGGGCCCUCUGUUCCUCUCCCACGGCAGAUGCCCUCCUCUGUAUGCAAAUCAGCACAGCCUUUAUUGAGCUUUACAACUAACAACCUGAUAGUUGGCAGUUAAUUCACAGUUACAGAUAAUGCUUUUAUUUACAUAAAUAUACCAAGUAGUACCCUCUUAUUGUAUUCACUUCAUCUAUUUUCUUAGAAUACUUGCAAUUACUAAUGACCCCUUCCCUUUCCCUCCUGCUGCCCUGUCCACCCUCUUUCCCCUUCUAACAUCCUUAGAGGGAUGAAAUCUCAGCAUAUGUUGCAGGACACCAAAAGGAAGAAAACAAUCAAGCAAAUAAAAUAAACAGUCAAACAAACCAGGAGUUUAAAACAACAACCCCAACAACAGAAGCCUUGGCAAAGAGGAAUAAGUGAUCAGCAAGUGAACACACUCUAUGUCAACUCUCCUUUUAUCCAGCUGAGAUUUAUGGUAACUUAUUUAAUUAAUGGUCCUGUCUGAUGCAUCCUUGAUGGCAAGCUUCAAAUCUGAUUUGGUAUCACCGAGGAAACCUUGCCCCCAUCACUCAGCAUUGCACUUAGAUACAGAAUGAGUUAGAUAAACUUGGCUUGUCUAGAGACCCAUGUCAUCUUAACCUAAAGGGAAAUCUUAUUGCGUUAUCAUAAAAUUGAUGAUAUCUUAGGGUCAGAAUUGCCCUUUUUUUUUAUUUUGAAUGGGAAGUUCUCACUAAAACAAUCCUGAGAUUUCUUAAUUUCAUGGUUCUUUAAAUAUUAUAAACACAGAGUCAACAUAGAAUGAAAUUGUAUUUGUUAAAAUACACACAUUGGAGGACAAGAGCAGAUGACUACUUUUCGAAGUAAUGCUGCUCCUUCCUAAAAGUCUGUUUUCAAUCCUGGUAAUAUUAGGGGCACUGCGGCACCUAAGAAGCCUUAAAUGAGAGCUAAUCCAAUCUAGAGAGCGAUGGUGUCAGCAUUUCGGUCUGCAUAUCUGUGUGUCCGUAUCUGCGUUUGUGUGCGUGUACGUGUGCCCCUGUGUGUGGGCCCAGUUUUCAGGCAUGUAGAAUAAGCAUGGAGUCAUAUUGAGGAGGACUCACUUCUUGAAGAUAUGCUUGUUGCUUUACAACAUAUGUAAGCUAUUCUUUAGCAUAAAUGCAUUCAUUCUUUAAUAAAAAUAUGUUUGCAUUAAUAAAGCUGAGGAGUUUCAUA